GCUCGGGGCCCGCUUCUCGGAGGGGCUGUCAUGGCCUACGGCGCUCCGAGCCCCACUUGGAGUCUGUCAGUUCGUCCGAAUAGACCCCGCGGCGGCCUGGGGCCAUUUGGAGAGGGACGAGGGGCAUCAUGGCAGAACAGGAUGUGGAAAACGAUCUUUUGGAUUACGAUGAAGAGGAAGAGCCCCAGGCUCCUCAAGAGAGCACACCAGCUCCCCCUAAGAAAGACAUCAAGGGAUCCUACGUUUCCAUCCACAGCUCUGGCUUCCGGGACUUUCUGCUGAAGCCGGAGCUCCUGCGGGCCAUCGUGGACUGUGGCUUUGAGCAUCCUUCUGAGGUCCAGCAUGAGUGCAUUCCCCAGGCCAUCCUGGGCAUGGACGUCCUGUGCCAGGCCAAGUCCGGGAUGGGCAAGACAGCGGUCUUCGUGCUGGCCACCCUACAGCAGAUUGAGCCUGUCAACGGACAGGUGACGGUCCUGGUCAUGUGCCACACGAGGGAGCUGGCCUUCCAGAUCAGCAAGGAAUAUGAGCGCUUUUCCAAGUACAUGCCCAGCGUCAAGGUGUCUGUGUUCUUCGGUGGUCUCUCCAUCAAGAAGGAUGAAGAAGUGUUGAAGAAGAACUGUCCCCAUGUCGUGGUGGGGACCCCGGGCCGCAUCCUGGCGCUCGUGCGGAAUAGGAGCUUCAGCCUAAAGAAUGUGAAGCACUUUGUGCUGGACGAGUGUGACAAGAUGCUGGAGCAGCUGGACAUGCGGCGGGAUGUGCAGGAGAUCUUCCGCCUGACACCACACGAGAAGCAGUGCAUGAUGUUCAGCGCCACCCUGAGCAAGGACAUCCGGCCUGUGUGCAGGAAGUUCAUGCAGGAUCCCAUGGAGGUGUUUGUGGACGACGAGACCAAGCUCACGCUGCACGGCCUGCAGCAGUACUACGUCAAACUCAAAGACAGUGAGAAGAACCGCAAGCUCUUUGAUCUCUUGGAUGUGCUGGAGUUUAACCAGGUGAUAAUCUUCGUCAAGUCAGUGCAGCGCUGCAUGGCCCUGGCCCAGCUCCUCGUGGAGCAGAACUUCCCGGCCAUCGCCAUCCACCGGGGCAUGGCCCAGGAGGAGCGCCUGUCACGCUAUCAGCAGUUCAAGGAUUUCCAGCGGCGGAUCCUGGUGGCCACCAAUCUGUUUGGCCGGGGGAUGGACAUCGAGCGAGUCAACAUCGUCUUUAACUACGACAUGCCUGAGGACUCGGACACCUACCUGCACCGGGUGGCCCGGGCGGGUCGCUUUGGCACCAAAGGCCUAGCCAUCACUUUUGUGUCUGACGAGAAUGAUGCCAAAAUCCUCAAUGACGUCCAGGACCGGUUUGAAGUUAAUGUGGCAGAACUUCCAGAGGAAAUCGACAUCUCCACAUACAUCGAGCAGAGCCGGUAACCACCACGUGCCAGAGCCGCCCACCCGGAGCCGCCCGCAUGCAGCUUCACCUCCCCUUUCCAGGCGCCACUGUUGAGAAGCUAGAGAUUGUAUGAGAAUAAACUUGUUAUUAUGGAAGCCUGGCUCCCACCCCAUCUA